UUUCUUUUUCUUUUCUUGCCUAUGUUUUUAGUGUCAUAUCUAAGAAAUCAUUGCCUAAUCUAAGAUCAUGAAGAAGUUCCUUUAUGUUUUCUUCUAAGAGUUUUAUAGUUUUAGCCCUUAUAUUUGGGUCUUUGAUUCAUUUUGAGUUAAUUUCCACAUAUCAAAUCCUGCUUUUAACGUCUAUAUUAUUUUGUCUUCUGAGGACAAAGACAGUCAUAGGACAUUUCUGAACUGGAUUUGAAUCCCCUGUCCCUCAGGAGUCAAUGUAAAUAUUCGUCUUGUCUAGCUUCUAGCAUCCACCUGCUCCACCUUGAGUUGGGUUAGCUGCUACCUUCUCUGAGCUCCCAGGGUGGUGAGACGCAGCCCUAAUGCAGGACUUAUCACUGUCUAAAGCAUUAUAGCCUGAAUCUCUCUCCCUUGUAAUACCAGGGACAUGUCUCUCUCCAUUAAUUUAUUAUGUUUCCAAAUAUUUGGAGCAUCUACCAUAAUUUUAUCUCUUGCUCAUCAUUUUCCAGCCUAUACUAAGAUUCUUAGUUGAUUAUAGGCUCUCAAAUACUUACAGAUUUGAAUUAAUAAUCAUAAUAACAACUUAAACUUAUUGAGCAUCUACUCUCUGCCGGGUAUGUGAUUAAACCCUUUGCAUGGGUCAUACUGAUCCAAUCCACAGCUCUUUUUGGAUAGGUACUAUUGUAGUCAUCUUCACAUAAUAGAUGCAGCAAAGAGAGGCUAAAACAAUCUCAAGGUCACAUAAAAGUAAUAGCAGGGCUAGUGUUUAACCCAGGCAGUUCACGUGCAGAGCCAAUGCUCCUAGCUGGUCUGUUACAAGUUCCACUUGAGGGACUGAGAGCAGCUCAGUAAAACAAAUUCCCAGUAAAACUCCCUUGUUCCAGGGCUUAAUCCUGGAAUCUCAGAGUCCUCCCUCACACACAGUGUGGAAAUCCCUUCAGAGGUCUCUGAAAGGCUUUUGAUCACCCACAUACUCUCUGUCUCCCUACCUCUUGGAGCGGCUUAUUCUAUUGUUGAUGGGCUUCAGGUGUGAUUUACACAUUCAACAAGAUCUGAGAUAGAUUUGGACAGAAGUCCUACCUUCGGGGCUUCCUGGUUAUGUGACCUUGGGCAUAUUUAACCCCCACUACCUCAACUGCAAAAUGGGGAGCACAAUACCAUGCAUGGCAUUGAGUUGUGAAGCUUCCAUGAGGCGAUGUUCAAGGCCUGGUGCAUUUGAAGAACUCAAUGACUGUUGGGUAUUGUUGCAUCAUAAACUCAUCAUUUCAGUGUCUGUCUCCUUCCUGUGACUGGGCUGUGCACUCCUGGAGGAUAUAAGAUGGUGUUUUGUUCAUCUUAGCACAGGGAUUGGCACUUGGUAGACACCCACUGGAUGCUUGUUGAAUGAACAAAUGAAUGAAUGGACAAAUGAACAGGGCCUCAAGUGAACAAACAAAUGGCAGUGCUAAUGUGGGAACCUGGGACAAGACUUGGUGAUUUGUAAGCCCCCAGGCAGAGGUGGUAAAGCACCUUUUGUUAUGUGUAUUCAAGCAUCCAUCCAGCCAAAAGUGCUGGAUUCAGGAAAGAUGGCAUCUAGCCCAGUGAGGUGAGGAAACUGAGGCCCAGAGAGGACAGGUCACUUGAGCAACGUCACACAGGUGGAAGGAGGAUUGUAGAACCUGUGCUUUUUAACAACUGCUGCUGCUGUGACUCACCAGAGUCUGAGUAUUGAGAAGAAAGAACACACUGAAGGCAGAAGAGUCAGAAAGAGCUGAGCGAGUUUGAGACGGGCCAACUCAGUCCAGGCCUCCAGACCUGCCCCAGGCUCGGUGCAGAGCCCAGCGCCACCUCAGCCUGGGCAGCCAGGGACCCCAGGAGGAAGCAGACCGGGUCCUGGGCCAGCAGGACGCUUUCCAGAUCAGAAGCCAGAGGUGGCUCCGAGCGACCCUGGGACCACUGCCCCACCCCGAGAGGAGAGAACAGGGGGAGUCGGGGGCUACCCAGCAGUUGGAGCCAGAGAGGACCGAAUGAGCCACCCCUCCGGACCCUAUUCCCAAGCAUCUGCAGCUGCCCCCCAGCCUGCUGCAGCCCGCCAGCCACCACCCCCAGAGGAGGAGGAAGAGGAAGCCAACAGCUACGAUUCGGAUGAAGCAACCACCCUGGGUGCCCUGGAAUUCAGCCUUCUCUACGACCAGGACAACAGCUCCCUGCAGUGCACCAUCAUUAAGGCCAAGGGCCUGAAGCCCAUGGAUUCAAACGGCUUGGCUGAUCCCUACGUUAAGCUGCACCUCCUGCCGGGAGCCAGCAAGUCCAACAAGCUUCGUACAAAAACUCUGCGGAAUACCCGGAACCCCAUCUGGAAUGAGACCCUCGUGUAUCACGGCAUCACCGAUGAGGACAUGCAAAGGAAGACCCUCAGGAUCUCCGUCUGUGAUGAGGACAAAUUUGGCCACAAUGAAUUUAUUGGUGAGACCAGAUUCUCCCUCAAGAAACUGAAGCCCAACCAGAGGAAGAAUUUCAACAUCUGCCUGGAGCGAGUGAUUCCUAUGAAACGUGCUGGGACCACCGGGUCAGCCCGAGGCAUGGCCCUUUAUGAGGAAGAGCAGGUGGAGCGUGUUGGUGACAUCGAGGAGCGUGGCAAGAUCCUGGUCUCCCUCAUGUACAGCACACAGCAGGGAGGCCUCAUUGUGGGCAUCAUACGCUGCGUGCACCUGGCUGCCAUGGACGCUAAUGGCUACUCAGACCCAUUCGUCAAGCUCUGGCUGAAACCGGACAUGGGAAAGAAGGCCAAACACAAGACUCAAAUUAAAAAGAAAACCUUGAAUCCCGAAUUCAAUGAGGAGUUUUUCUAUGACAUCAAACACAGUGACCUGGCAAAGAAGUCACUGGACAUUUCAGUCUGGGACUAUGACAUCGGCAAGUCCAAUGAUUACAUCGGAGGCUGCCAGCUGGGGAUCUCUGCCAAGGGAGAGCGCUUAAAACACUGGUACGAGUGUCUGAAAAAUAAAGACAAGAAGAUAGAGCGCUGGCACCAGCUACAGAAUGAGAACCACGUGUCAAGUGAUUAGGCUAGUGCCCAGGUCCCCAUCUCCAUGUCCCGGGUCCCCCCCAGCCUGCUCUAGCUGCCCACCGCACCCUGAUCUCUCUUCUCUAUGCCUACCUCCCCCCAUACCCUGCUGAUCUCCCUGAGCCUGCCUUUGAGCCCCCGUCACGUUGGGCACUGCUGCCAAAGACUCCCUCCUCCCUGAUGCUGGGAUGUGGGCUCUGAAUACAGCCCCUCUCUCAUCCCUGGGAUGGAGCAAUGGGGAUGGGGUUGGGGAGACGUUUACAAAGAGGUUGAUCAUUUAAUAACCUCUCAGUUUGGGUAAAUUACAAAGGUUCUUCAUCAUUUAGGACUGUUUUUAGACCCUCCUAGCCUUGAACACACACAUGUACACACACACACACACACACACACACACACCCUUUCAUUCCCUGUGUUGUGUCUCUGUAUAUCCCCAGUUGUCAGCAGACCCGGACAAUGCUGUGAGAGAAGCAUUGGGGCACAAAUAGAGCCUCCGGGCUCCCACUGCCCCCUGAGAUGUACACCCUGAUUGCCAGGAAAACAGACUGCUGUGUUCAGUAACACACCCUCCCUGCUCCAAGUGCACCAGGAUGCAAAUGCACAGAAUUCACCAGGGGCUUGGACGCUCUCCUCUUUCCGAAUGUCACCUGUGUGCUUCCUAGCAAAACAAAAACAAACGACAACAACAAAAAACCCUUCCUCUGUCACCUUUUCUCCUCCUCCCUCUUCUUUCCCUUCCAUGAUAGUAGAUUCUCUCUUUCUCAGCCUCUCCCCUCUCCUUUCUCUCCCUGCCUUUCUUCCCUUUGCCUUUCUCUCUCUCUAAAGCAGUAACACCGCAAAAACAACAGCAAAAAAAGUGUAUGUUAACCUAGCCUCACCCCCUUGCUCUCACCAGCCUGACCAGGAAACUGAGAAACUGGCCCAAACCUGAGAUUCCACUUGGGCCCACGCUUCUUAACUGACCCACUCCUCCCGUUGGCAGAACCAGACAUUCCCAGGGCUUGGGCCAAUGGCUGGCACUGCCCUGAGUGCAUGGCAGCAUCCCUCAAGCUGUGUAGAUGCCCCAUAGAGGACUCUCUCAUCCGUGGGCUCCCCGGGUGGGCACGGAGGCAUUUAGAAGACCAGGGCCAUGGGUCUGAGGAAGCCUCAGCCAAAGCCUCCAGCCUUUCUCCUUUCUCCGCUCUUAGGUAAAUGAACAAGCUACCCUCCUCCCCAAUGCCCUUGACUCUGUUUCAUUGACUCUUUUGCAUCCCAUCUCUCACUCAGAACCCCCUCCAGUCUCUCUGUCUCUCUUUGUCUGUCUCUCUGUCUCCUGCACUCUCGUUACUAAGCUUCCUGGGAGAAUCAAAUAAUAUCAUGGCUAUGGAACAGUAGAGAGAGACAGGCCUGAUGCCAAAGGCUUUGGGCUCAUCAUCAAUCUUUCACUUUCUUCCUAUAAAAAAAAUUAUUUUAUAAAGGAGGAAAAGGCAAUGUGGGCAAACAUUACAAAUUUGAGGUUGAAGUCAGGCAAUCUUCAAUGCCCUGUGAGAAAGGUUCGAUUUUCCCAAUUUUGAUGAAGUCUUCCCUCAUGAAAAUCACUCCCAGUCAUCCCAAACCCCUGACAUUCUCUACAGAAGCAUCAGACAGAUACUCAAACUCUCACUUUCCCCAAAUCACAUCUCUUAACUUUUCAACGCCCUCCACCCUCAGCUCCCUGCACAAUUCAUGGGAGGACUCAUUUCUUGCCUUGAAUAACCAUUUUCUAAACAUCGAGCUCUUCACCUUCCCCAAGGUGGCCAACAGCUUCCUGGCUGCCAUCUUUCCUUUUGACCUUAUCUUUCCCCAUUAGUCCCUGGUGGCACCUACUCUCAGCCCACCUCCCUCACCACAGUUUCCCCUUAGGAGACAGCAUGCUGGCUGUGUCGCCCAAGCCUGAUGCUGGUGUAGGCGCUGGAAUCAGCAUGCAGCAAGCUCACAGUGCCCCUAGUCUGGGUGCCCGCUGUCCCCGACAAAUGUAACCACCUCCCUGCCUAGAAUACACACACGUCCUCCGGUGCAUGCACAACCACCCAGCAUCUUUCUUUGUGAUGAUGUAGCCAAAAAUAAAGUAGGAGCAUCCAAGAAAA